AGGCAGCGCUGUGCUCAGGGGCCAUUUUGAACAGUGAAACCACCAACAAAAAGCAUAAAAAUGUGAAGAACGUGGUACAAAAUUGAUGGCAAAAAGGACACCUGUUUACAGGAUAAGGGCUGAAACGAGAAGGCCUAGUGUCACCUUGUUUGACCUCAGUGAGCCAUCAACCUAAUAACAAGAGAGAGCAACAAGGCCUGGGGUCCCUUUGCUGGAGCACAGUCCCAAGGUGCAUCCGUCUGUGACCCAGGGAAACACCUCGAAGAGAAAAGUAGCUAUCUUCAAGCGACUAAAACUGAAGUAUAAUAAGAGAACCAUGUGAUUCAAGCAAGUCCACAACAGAGCCAACAGAGUCUGCUUUCAAAGGAAUCUGCAAAUUGAAGGAUACAAACAGAAUGGAUUAUUUGCUCAUGAUUUUCUCUCUGCUGUUUGUGGCUUGCCAAGGAGCUCCAGAAACAGCAGUCUUAGGCGCUGAGCUCAGCGCGGUGGGUGAGAACGGCGGGGAGAAACCCACUCCCAGUCCACCCUGGCGGCUCCGCCGGUCCAAGCGCUGCUCCUGCUCGUCCCUGAUGGAUAAAGAGUGUGUCUACUUCUGCCACCUGGACAUCAUUUGGGUCAACACUCCCGAGCACGUUGUUCCGUAUGGACUUGGAAGCCCUAGGUCCAAGAGAGCCUUGGAGAAUUUACUUCCCACAAAGGCAACAGACCGUGAAAAUAGAUGCCAAUGUGCUAGCCAAAAAGACAAGAAGUGCUGGAAUUUUUGCCAAGCAGGAAAAGAACUCAGGGCUGAAGACAUUAUGGAGAAAGACUGGAAUAAUCAUAAGAAAGGAAAAGACUGUUCCAAGCUUGGGAAAAAGUGUAUUUAUCAGCAGUUAGUGAGAGGAAGAAAAAUCAGAAGAAGUUCAGAGGAACACCUAAGACAAACCAGGUCGGAGACCAUGAGAAACAGCGUCAAAUCAUCUUUUCAUGAUCCCAAGCUGAAAGGCAAGCCCUCCAGAGAGCGUUAUGUGACCCACAACCGAGCACAUUGGUGACAGACCUUCGGGGCCUGUCUGAAGCCAUAGCCUCCACGGAGAGCCCUGUGGCCGACUCUGCACUCUCCACCCUGGCUGGGAUCAGAGCAGGAGCAUCCUCUGCUGGUUCCUGACUGGCAAAGGACCAGCGUCCUCGUUCAAAACAUUCCAAGAAAGGUUAAGGAGUUCCCCCAACCAUCUUCACUGGCUUCCAUCAGUGGUAACUGCUUUGGUCUCUUCUUUCAUCUGGGGAUGACAAUGGACCUCUCAGCAGAAACACACAGUCACAUUCGAAUUCGGGUGGCAUCCUCCGGAGAGAGAGAGAGGAAGGAGAUUCCACACAGGGGUGGAGUUUCUGACGAAGGUCCUAAGGGAGUGUUUGUGUCUGACUCAGGCGCCUGGCACAUUUCAGGGAGAAACUCCAAAGUCCACACAAAGAUUUUCUAAGGAAUGCACAAAUUGAAAACACACUCAAAAGACAAACAUGCAAGUAAAGAAAAAAAAAAGAAAGACUUUUGUUUAAAUUUGUAAAAUGCAAAACUGAAUGAAACUGUUACUACCAUAAAUCAGGAUAUGUUUCAUGAAUAUGAGUCUACCUCACCUAUAUUGCACUCUGGCAGAAGUAUUUCCCACAUUUAAUUAUUGCCUCCCCAAACUCUUCCCACCCCUGCUGCCCCUUCCUCCAUCCCCCAUACUAAAUCCUAGCCUCGUAGAAGUCUGGUCUAAUGUGUCAGCAGUAGAUAUAAUAUUUUCAUGGUAAUCUACUAGCUCUGAUCCAUAAGAAAAAAAAGAUCAUUAAAUCAGGAGAUUCCCUGUCCUUGAUUUUUGGAGACACAAUGGUAUAGGGUUGUUUAUGAAAUAUAUUGAAAAGUAAGUGUUUGUUACGCUUUAAAGCAGUAAAAUUAUUUUCCUUUAUAUAACCGGCUAAUGAAAGAGGUUGGAUUGAAUUUUGAUGUACUUAUUUUUUUAUAGAUAUUUAUAUUCAAACAAUUUAUUCCUUAUAUUUACCAUGUUAAAUAUCUGUUUGGGCAGGCCAUAUUGGUCUAUGUAUUUUUAAAAUAUGUAUUUCUAAAUGAAAUUGAGAACAUGCUUUGUUUUGCCUGUCAAGGUAAUGACUUUAGAAAAUAAAUAUUUUUUUCCUUACUGUA